UUCUGCUCCCAAGGUGAUAGGAGAAAACACCAGAGAGAUGAGGUCUCAGAGUCAGAGACAUCAGUCACAGAAAGAAAGAUGGAAAGUCAGAGGGCAGUGGGGGUCUGGGGGGCUGGAGGCACCACUUACCUCAGUCACUGGCCCUGUCUUUGUGCCCCAGGUCCGAAGCCCCAGAAGGACUCUGUCUCAGACUGGGCCAUUGUGUUGAUCACUCUCACUUUGGUGGCAGCAAUUGUCAGCCUAAUGUACGGUAUCAAGAAGGCCUGCCAGUUCCGGAGGGAGAUGAGUCUGGGGUGUGGCUGUGGCUCUGUGACCCCUUACAGCAGCCACCAUGAGGGGGAGGCUGCCAGCCAGCGCUACUCUUGUCAAAUGAAAGGUAGAUUCCUGGGGUCACUGGCCCCCCCAGGUCUCUUCCACCCACAGCGUAAGGAGGAGUCUACUGUCAGUCACAAGAUUCUGCUCUCUGUCCUGCCGCCAGCCAUGCAGACUGCGGGAAGGUGCCCAGCUUCUCCGAGGGCAGUUUUCUCAUCUGUAGAAGGAAGGACCAGGGCUAAGUGGUCUGCAGGCACCUUCCAGCCCUCACGGAGCCCAGGUCUGGACAGCUGGAACCCCUGCCCCUCACCCUCUCUUCCUAGUCCCACCCUCCUCCCUGACGACCAGAGAAGCUCUUUAGCUGAGGACAGUCUGCUCACGGCUUCCCUUCUCACUUCCCUCCACAGGGAGCCCCCUCAGGCUGGCUCUUGAGCCCCCAAGGCCCUCUGAUUCUCUCCCCUCAGGGCAGGUGCAGGACCCUCCUCUGUGGUGCCCCCUCGGUCUGCUAUGGGAGGGUGGUGAACAAGUUAUUGCUAAAUAAAAUGGCACUUCCUCCACUUGUCUCCCAGAUGCUGUGGGUUUGCCCAAGUGCAUGGGCUUUUGUGUCAUGUGGGCCCGGAAGGGCCAAGUCUGGUCUCUGCCAGUUACCAGGGCAAGUCAUUCCCUGAUCCGA